CAUUCUCCUGCCUCAGCCUCCCACAUUUCUAAGAAUCCAGAAGACUUAAAUAUAAGAUGCAAAAUGGCUUUAACCUAGUUACUGUUAAUUCUGAAAUCGUCACAUAAAAUCUCAAAACAGACUGUGGAGUCUGAGAAACUUCGAUUCAUCUGCAAAUCCAUCAUAUUCUAGGCAAUUUACUUAACAUCUGAUGGCCUCCAUUUCCUCAUCUGUGAAAUGGGGAUUAUAAAUAAGCACCUGAUAGGGUUGCCUUGACAAUUUAAUGAUAGAAUAUAUGUAAAGUUUCUCAAAUGGCUGGAUAUAACAGACAUUCAAUAAAGGUUCCCCAUCCCUUACCCAUGUCUAUAUAUAUCUACUAUUUGCUUCAUGUUUUAAGUGCUGAGGCAAAAAUAAGAUUGAAUAAUUAAGGCAAUGAGCAUUCUUGAGAUAUAAUUAGUAUGUAUUAUAUUAUUAUAAUAUAUUCUUACAAUAUAAUUAGUAUAUAGUAUAUAGCAAAGAGCCAUAAUACUAAGUAAUGAUAAUAAUAAUACCCAUUGAAGACUUACUUUUGUGUCAGGCACUAUGUUUUACAUGCAUUUAAUUUCAUCUAAUUUCAGAUCAGUUCUGCGAUUUAGGCAUUAUUGUCAUCAUCCUCAUCCCCAUUUUACAGAUGAAAUACUGAGGCUUAGAAAGACUGAUUGCCCAAGUACCAUCUAACACCAAUCUUGGUCUGCUAACUCCUAAUUCCAUUGACUAGGUGCUUUGACUGGUUGGAAUCAGUGAAGAAAACAAGGAAGAUGGUAAUAUCCCUGUCUUAGCUUAGAGAGAUGGUGUAUCAAAAAAAGCUACAAGUAAGGGCCCUAGACCUGCACUGUCCAGUAUAGUAGCUACUAACCACAUGGAGCUAUUAAGGACUUGAAAUGUGGCUCUCAUCUGGGUGCAGUGCUUGCUCUACUACUUACUAGCUUUGCCUAUAGCAACUUACUUACCCUCUGUGCCUUUCUUCUGAAAAUGGGGAUAAUAGCACCUACUUCAUAGGGCCAUUGUGAAAUAAAGGAAUUGAUAUAUAUGUAAUAGGCUCAGUGUCACCAGUCCAUAAGAAGCUCUCUCUAUAUGCUUAAAAGAGGAAAAUCAGCAAGACUUAGUGGUCUACCUGAUUGUAGAGGUCAAGAAAGAGGAGGUGUCAUAGUAAGUCCAAGUUAGGAACUUAGGUGACUAGAAAGACUACUCACAAUGCCAUAAGAAAUGUGAAAAAGUUCUCAGGAGUCAACUCUUGCUCCUUGCAAACUUAUGUUUGCUAAACAACUCCAUUUACAUAUGAAAGUUUUCAUCCAUAAUCAAAGGGACACAGAAGACAGUCACAAUAUAUGAGAGAGCUGUUCCUUACAUGGUCCUGGCACAUCCACAAACCUAGCUUUUGCCUUUCAACUCCCACCCAUACUUAAACACCAGGCUUACUGGUCCUGAGUGACUUGCUGAGUGACCUGUGGUUGGAUUCAAUUUAUUGCAGCAUCAUUUCUAAUAGCAAAAGAUGAUAACCUAAACCUCCAUCAGUAGGAGGCUGGUCACAUUCAUCUAACAGAUCCUUAAGGCAGCUGAAUGAAGAGAGAGGUUUUAUAUACGAAUAUGGAACUGUUCACAAUGUGUACUUCUAAGAAGAAAAGAAAGGUAUGUAUAAUAAUGUUAAUUACUGUUUGCUAAAAAGAAAACAAAGAGGGGGUAAAUACAUAUAUUUGUUUGAAUAUGCAUGGAGUAUCUCUGGAAGGGGUAACAAGAAACUUACUCCUUGCCUUUGAGAAAAAAAACUAGGUGGCUGGGAUAUAGGGAUGAGAGAGAUUGACUUUUCUCUGUAUGUCUUUCUGUACCUUUUGAAUCUUAAAUCUUGUGAAUCUAAUACAUAAAGAUAAUCAAAAUUUCUGAUAAACUAGUUUCCAGUUGGAAAGUGUAAAGGGGGAGUUAGUUAAUUGAGGGAAGAUGGCAUAAGGAAUGGGAAGAUGACUGGAAUGGCUCACAGGAGCUACUUGGAGAUGGAGGCUCAAACUCUGGUUUUCAGGCUAAAUGUCUAUUGCAUAAAUUAUUUUUUCUGUCCUCUAAUUUUAAGAAAAAGGCAAAUGCAAAUCACUGUUUUAAGGUACCACCUAAUAAAAAUUCAACUGCCAUUUUAUUAGGUUCAGGUGAACAUUUCUGUGGGAACUCAGCUGUCUGCUCUCCUGCUAUCAUGCUAUCAGGCUGGUAAACCACUUAAGAAAAAAAGAUGCCUCUGUGUUUGGAGAUCUCAUUCUAGUUAUGGAAAUAAAUAUGUGAACUCCUGAUUAUACGACGUGAUGAGGCCUGUAAUAGAGGGAUGUGCUGGGGAACUAGUUAUACCUAGUGGGAGGGGCUGGUCAGGAAGGUCUCAGACAUGGAAGUAGCAUUGGCACAGACCUGGAAAGAUAAGUUUAGUAGGCAGAGAGCUUCUAUCCAGAUAAAAGAAGGGACAAGGUGAAGGAGGAAGGUGUGCAGGUAUGACGGUGUAUUCAAAGAGCAGCAAGUCACUCAGGGCCAGUAAGCCUGGUGUUUAAGUAUGAGUGGGAGUCGAAAGGCAAAAGUUAGGUUUGUGGAUGUGCAAGGACCAUGUAAGGAACAGCUCUCACACAUUGUGGCUGUCUUCUGUGUCCCUUUGAUUAUGGAUGAAAACUUUCCAUAUGUAAAUGGAGUUGUUAAGCAAACAUAAGUUUGCAAGGAGCAAGAGUUGACUCCUGAGAAAUAGCCGAAUGUGGGACAUAUAGAGCAUGUUCUAGAAGAGGUGAGGAUAUGAGAAAAGAUAUGACAGACAGACAGAUGAACAGGGAACCUAAGGAUACUAAGGAUACUCGAGAGUUAACAUUGGAGCCAGGCUGAGGGUAGGAACUCAGGAGAUAUUUUAGAUAAAGGAGCCCAGAAGCACUGGGCAACUGGCUUGGCUGUUGGUCUUUGGUCUUUUAUUUCUGCAUCCUUUAUUUCUAUAGCCACUAGCCUUUGCCCCUGAGACACUGCCUUGACUUGAUUGGCGUUAGCAGACUGUACCAGCACACUGGGUGCCUCUGUGUGGCUUGUACCUUAGAGCUCCUGCCUCUGGUCCAGUAGGUGAUGGCUCCCAUCUGCUUUAUUCUAUGACAGUUGCAGGAAAGGUGUGCAGAACUGGUUCAGAAGCCCAGACUAAAAAAAACCCUCAAUUUUCUUAGUGAUGAUAGAAGUUACCCAUGGGAGAUUCGGGGCCCUCAGUUUGGCAGUGCCUCCUACUGCCAUCACAGGCUACAGUGAUCUUGUAAAAGGGUUACACAACCAUGGAGGAGCUAAGGGAGCCUUCUGGCUUACCUGUCACAUUAGUGCUGAGGGCUCUUUCUCUGUUCACCAUUUGGUAUGGCAUUGCCAAUAUUCUUGUUUGCCUCUCUGUAGCCAAAGUUGCUUAUUGCAUAUAGCUCAUUCCAUGAGAGUUUAGACUAGAUAAUUAUAUAGGCAGCUUCAUUUAAAAUGCUAAUAACCUUACCUAAAUAGAGCAUAUUUCUAGCACAAUUGGAUUGGGCAGCUCUCCAGGCUAGAUCCCUUGAUUCAAGUUACAUGAUCAUUUUUUUUUUUUAAUCAGCAUUGGGAGAAUCCUUCCCCUUCUUUGGGUAGAAAAGAGCUUCUUGUUUUUGUUCUAUUUUGAAAUACGUAUAUCCAAUCAACCAGCUUAUUUGGAGCCUUCUUCUGUGUGUUAGGCAUUCUACUAAAUGCUGAGUAGAUACUAAGAUAAAGUCCCCAGUAAGAUCUUCAGUGAACUUACUGUCUAGUGGGUGGGAGGAAGUAGUGGAACAGAUGCAAACACAAAGAAGUAUUAGAAAAUCUGGUCAGUACCAUGAUAGAACUCUGUUUGGGUAUUCUGGGAGCCCAGAAAGGGUGUUCAUCGCCAUGGGAAGCAGGGAGCUAUGGCAAGAAGUGACAUCAAAGUGAUGGGGAGGAGUUGACCAGGCGGGAGUGUAAGGGGCAAUGGGAGCAACAGCACUGAGGUGAGGAGCAGUCAAUUUGCUGUGUUUAUGGAACUAAAAUUCAUCUGGUGUAGCCCAAGUGGCAAGGCCAGGGCUGGCAAGAAGAAGAUUGGAGAGGUGGGCGGGAGCUAGAUCACAGGAAACUUUUUACUGGACUUCAUCCUGCAGGUGGGAGAUAGAAAGCCAUCCUGUUUAGGGAGACAGGUUGUGGAGAGUAUUAAGGACAAGAGCCUGAGGGUCAGAAUUGGAAAGGAGCUCAGCUGGAUGGAAACAUAGAAGGCAGACGAGAGUUGCAUACAUGUCUGGAGGGCCUGGGCCUGAAAAGGAAACUGCGUGAAAGUUUAUAUUUGGUUUUUAGGGCAAAGAGAUUGAAAGAGGGGAGUCACAUAAUCAGCAUACGUUUAUGAAGAUUACCCCCACAGCUGUGUGGCAAGUGAUCAAAAAGGAACAGGACCAGAGAAGAGCAGGAAAACUGGUCAGAAAGCAGGCGCCCUAACCCUGGUGAGCAGUGAUGAGAUCCUGGAAGUGGAGGUGGCAGAAUGUGGGAAGGAUUGCCCCCUGUGGGUCACUUUCUCAGUCAUUUUGAGCUCAGCCUAAUCAAAGACUGAGGUUAUGAAGUCGAUCCUAGAUGGCCUUGCAGAUACCACCUUCCGCACCAUCACCACUGACCUCCUGUACGUGGGCUCAAAUGACAUUCAGUACGAAGACAUCAAAGGUGACAUGGCAUCCAAAUUAGGGUACUUCCCACAGAAAUUCCCUUUAACUUCCUUUAGGGGAAGUCCCUUCCAAGAGAAGAUGACUGCGGGAGACAACCCCCAGCUAGUCCCAGCAGACCAGGUGAACAUUACAGAAUUUUACAACAAGUCUCUCUCGUCCUUCAAGGAGAAUGAGGAGAACAUCCAGUGUGGGGAGAACUUCAUGGACAUAGAGUGUUUCAUGGUCCUGAACCCCAGCCAGCAGCUGGCCAUUGCAGUCCUGUCCCUCACGCUGGGCACCUUCACGGUCCUGGAGAACCUCCUGGUGCUGUGCGUCAUCCUCCACUCCCGCAGCCUCCGCUGCAGGCCUUCCUACCACUUCAUCGGCAGCCUGGCGGUGGCAGACCUCCUGGGGAGUGUCAUUUUUGUCUACAGCUUCAUUGACUUCCACGUGUUCCACCGCAAAGAUAGCCGCAACGUGUUUCUGUUCAAACUGGGUGGGGUCACGGCCUCCUUCACUGCCUCCGUGGGCAGCCUGUUCCUCACAGCCAUCGACAGGUACAUAUCCAUUCACAGGCCCCUGGCCUAUAAGAGGAUUGUCACCAGGCCCAAGGCCGUGGUGGCGUUUUGCCUGAUGUGGACCAUAGCCAUUGUGAUCGCCGUGCUGCCUCUCCUGGGCUGGAACUGCGAGAAACUGCAAUCUGUUUGCUCAGACAUUUUCCCACACAUUGAUGAAACCUACCUGAUGUUCUGGAUCGGGGUCACCAGCGUACUGCUUCUGUUCAUCGUGUAUGCGUACAUGUAUAUUCUCUGGAAGGCUCACAGCCACGCCGUCCGCAUGAUUCAGCGUGGCACCCAGAAGAGCAUCAUCAUCCACACGUCUGAGGAUGGGAAGGUACAGGUGACCCGGCCAGACCAAGCCCGCAUGGACAUUAGGUUAGCCAAGACCCUGGUCCUGAUCCUGGUGGUGUUGAUCAUCUGCUGGGGCCCUCUGCUUGCAAUCAUGGUGUAUGAUGUCUUUGGGAAGAUGAACAAGCUCAUUAAGACGGUGUUUGCAUUCUGCAGUAUGCUCUGCCUGCUGAACUCCACCGUGAACCCCAUCAUCUAUGCUCUGAGGAGUAAGGACCUGCGACACGCUUUCCGGAGCAUGUUUCCCUCUUGUGAAGGCACUGCGCAGCCUCUGGAUAACAGCAUGGGGGACUCGGACUGCCUGCACAAACACGCAAACAAUGCAGCCAGUGUUCACAGGGCCGCAGAAAGCUGCAUCAAGAGCACGGUCAAGAUUGCCAAGGUAACCAUGUCUGUGUCCACAGACACGUCUGCCGAGGCUCUGUGAGCCUGAUGCCUCCCUGGCAGCACAGGAAAAGAAUUUUUUUUUUUAAGCUCAAAAUCUAGAAGAGUCUAUUGUCUCCUUGGUUAUAUUUUUUUAACUUUACCAUGCUCAAUGAAAAGGUGAUUGUCACCAUGAUCACUUAUCAGUUUGCUAAUGUUUCCAUAGUUUAGGUACUCAAACUCCAUUCUCCAGGGGUUUACAGUGAAGAAAGCCUGUUGUUUAAGUGACUGAACGAUCCUUCAAAGUCUCAAUGAAAUAGGAGGGAAACCUUUGGCUACACAAUUGGAAGUCUAAGAACCCAUGGAAAAAUGCCAUCAAAUGAAUAAUGCCUUUGUAACCACAACUUUCACUAUAAUGUGAAAUGUAACUGUCCGUAGUAUCAGAGAUGUCCAUUUUUACAAGUUAUAGUACUAGAGAUAUUUUGUAAAAUGUAUUAUGUCCUGUGAGAUGUGUAUCAGUGUUUAUGUGCUAUUAAUAUUUGUUUAGUUCAGCAAAACUGAAAGGUAGACUUUUAUGAGAACAAUGGACAAGCAGUGGAUACGUGUCAAUGUGUGCACUUUUUUUCUAUAUUAUUGCCCAUGAUAUAACUUUAGAAAUAAACCUUAAUAUUUCUUCAAAUAUCUCUAUUUAAUUUUGACACUGAAAUAACCGUAAAGGUUUAUUUUUCUGUUACCUCAACAAGAAGAAUUUGAAGACUUCAAAAUAUUGAGCAGAAUUCAUUCAUACUUAAAAAUUUAUUAGCCCUGCAUUUUCAUAGGAAGACACAUUAUCUUCUGGACUAUAGCUGUUCUAAUGGAUUAUAAUCAGAAUGGAAGAGAGAAAGCAUAUUGACUUUUUUUGAGCGACAUCUCUGACUUUCUUUAGUCUUUAGCUAUUACUGGAUCUCUUAAGACAGCAUGUGUUAAUCUUAAUGUAUAUCGUUAUCACUGUGCAGUUGCUGUUUACUUGAAUAGUAUUGUGUUCCUAUAUUCCAGGUUUAAGUAGAUUUCAUGCCUGGGUGGCCAAACAACAGUCUUCAUUUUUUUUAAUUGAAAAGAAGUAGUGUCUGGAUCAGUAAAAUUAUACUGUGUGUGAGUGUGAAUAUAAAUGUGUGUAUGUGUGUUUCUGUCCUGUAACUGUUACAGUAAUGUCAUAAAGUGAGAAAACUGUGACCAAGUAUAAACUUUUACCACUUGCUGCACUCUUGCACAUGGAUUCAGUUUCUAAAAUUGAGUUCUUCCUGUAAUCUUGUUGAUAAAAAUACUGACUCCAACCAUUCAAAAAUUUCACCCCAUCCCUCCUUAAGAGAUUGGAUCAAGUAUUACUAAAUUGACCUUUAGGUAUUACACAAGACCAGUGCUUAGCAAAAAAUAAUGACAGGCAUCCAAGGAAGGGAUGUAUUUGUAGUGUUAUUGCCAGGAAAGGAGAGUACUUUGGUUUCUGAGCACCGAAUAUUGAGCAAUAUGUCAGUCACUAAAAGGAAGACAGUUCUACAGAAAAACAAUGGUAACAUUUUUCAAUAGCGUGUGUAGAUAGUAUGCACUAUAUACAUCACGUUAAAGUAGGACUAUCACACCCAGCCCAUGUGGCUAAAAAAGCUGAAUCAGACAGUGGAUGAGACACACAACGGCAGUGAAGAACCGAUACACUUGGCAUUGACGUCUAGCUAUGCUGUAUCUGUGCUUUGCCCACAUGCCCUUGGUGACAGCUGAGCACCCAGCUCUGUCUUGGUAGGUUUGGGCUAAGGAACAAAUCUCUCCUUUGCUCGUGGUUAGCAAGAUACACUCAAGCAUGAAGAUAAACACAGCUGCUUUCUUCUUACACCCCGGUCUCAUGCUCCUUAAUGGCGCCAUGGGUGCUUGUUGGGCCUUUUUCCAGUAAGGAAUGAUAUUGCUGAAGAAUCUACUUAACCCUGACAAAUUUUAAUUAUAAUCUCUUCUUAUACAGAUAAAACAUGACUCCUACAAGGCCCCAAGGUUUACAUAGUCUGAAGUGAAGUACAGAGCUGGCAUCUAUCUGGUGAUUUCUAGCUCUCGAGAUACCCAAGCAGCCUGAUGGGGCAGUUCCCCUUCUUACGGUUCACGCUCUAAGGCAGGAUGUGGCUUAUGAGAUACUUUGCAUUGUCUGUCUGCACACCUUGAAUCUGCCUGCUGGCUCCCUUACUUUACCUCUCUGUCAUGUGCAGAUGAAGGCUCAGGGUGCUAGAGGAUUAGUAAGAUCUCUUUCUAAAGACAGGAGAGAUUAUUUACAAGAAGAACUCACCAGGGUUUAGUUUGCAUUUAAGAAUUGCCAGUCUUUUGUCCUGCAUCAUCUUGAACAUUAAUCCACAUGUUUCAGAGCUCACCAGGCAGUACCAAUGCUCUUUUCACAGCUAUGAAGAGCUAGAGAAAUUCUUGUUAUGGUAGAAAAAUUUCACGAUUCAUUUUUGAAACUGCAUUUGUGCGUAUGCAGUGUAGAUUUUAUAGUGUGUUGUGCUUUCAAGAUCUAAAUCAUAUAUAAUAAAUUAAGGGACAAUGGGGCUGACAGCACUAAACUUGGUGCUUAUUGAUAUUCUAAGAAAUAUCUGUGAAAUAUCAUCACGUAUGUUAUACAACCUUCAUUUAAAAAGGUUUAAAACUAGUUAGAUUCACUUUGACACUUUUCAUAUCAUUUCUUAACCCAAGUGACGAAAACAUUGUCCCCAAUGAAUAUACUCAUUAGAAUUACCAUUUGUUAAUAUCACUCAUUAAUUAACCCCAUAAUUAGAUCCAUUAAUUUAAAUGAUUUAAAUUUAAGUAAGUUUUAUAAGGUCUGACAUCAGAGGUAUCUUACUUUCCUCUGAGGAUGAUGUACUUGCCCUGACCAUGCAUUUUACCAUCACACAUGUUCAGAAAGGGCCAAAUUCCCAACCUGCUCAUUUUUUUUUUAUCAGAGUCAUGAUGAAUCAGUCCUAGAAUGUUUCAUUUGCACAAGUAGGGCUGCCUCCAAGAGGAACCUCUGAUUUAUUUUGUAUGAAAUAUAUGUGAAAGGAUAUGAAUCUGAGAGAUGCUGUAGACAUCUGUCCUACACUUGAGAUGAUUUCCAAGCCUCUCUGGCACUUUGAGUUAAGUCUAUCUGGUAUUAAAUGCCAAGGACCUUUUGCUGCCUAAAUCCACUCUGCAGGAAAUAGGCCCAACCACCAGAUGAGAAUUAGGCCCUGGAUGAGUAGCGCUAUAGUUACUGUCCUGUUGAUUAAUUUCUGCCAUUUCAUGUCCAUAAAAGAGACCACCCAUAUCAUGCACACAAUUAGAUUUCUCACACUCUAACUGUAUAUUUGUAUGAUAUUUUAAAAUCUCCUAAAUGCUGGGCAAUGGCUAUUAACAAUUAAUUGUCUUGCACUGGCCUUCUGAUGAAAUGUUAACAAUGCCUAUUGUAAUAUAGAAAAAAACAUUCUAUCUACUGAUUUGGGCUGAAUGUAUGUAAAUAGGUUUCUAAAAAGUCAGAUGUUUGAGCAGUGGCCUACAAAUCAGUAAUUUUCGGAUGGGAGAGUUUCUUUACAUUGCCGUGGCAUCUUAAAAGCUAUCUUCAUGUAAAUUGACUGUACUAGGCCUACUGGGGAUCAGAGUUCCCAAGAAAGGAAACCUUUUCUUGUAUCUGGAUUCAAAUUUAUUUCCAAUGUUUCAAGCGGGAAACAUGACUCUUUAUUGUCUGUAAAUCUAACAUUAUUACUUUUCCUCUUAGAAGAAUAUUGUAUUGUUAGAUGUUUGUUGAGCUGGUAACAUCGUUGCAACCACUGCAAUAUCUUCGUUAGUAAUCUGUAUAAUACUUUGUAUACAAGUACUGGUAAGAUUGUUAUUAAAUGUAGCUUCAGUCAUUAAAUUACUAUAGCAAAGUAGUACUUCUUCUGUAAUAUUUACAAUGUAUUAAGCCCACAGUAUAUUUUAUUUCAAUGUAAUUAAACUGUUAACUUAUUCAAAGAGAAAACAUCUCAUCAUGUCUAUUGUCCAAAGUUACCUGGAAUCAAAUAAAAAUUCUAGAUUACCAUGAAGAACAUAAAA